UGGCCAAGAACAUAUCAGCUUAAGUUUGGGAAAAACACACAACAGGGCAUUGUGUCAGAGGGUGACCAAAGUGACUCCCCAGCAGAUGGACCAGGGAACGAACAGGUGACCUUUGAACUGAGGCCGGAGUGGAAGCAGCGAGGGUGUGAAGGGCCGGGUGAGGGUCAAAGGCAGAAGCAAGCAGGUGGGGAGGGUUAGCGUCAUGCCUGCUAAGGAGCAGUGGACGGGUCCUAGCACGUGCUGUGAGCCACCCGCUGUCCAGGGAGCGGUUACCUCUGUCUUGCCAGCUUCGUGGGGACAGAUAGUUCAGCUCAUCAUUUAUGAGACAGAGAAUGGGAAUUUGGAGGGUCUGUGGCUGGCCUCGUCCUGGGUGCGCAGGGGGUCACCUGAGGUGUGGUCUGAGGCCUCCGGGGAAGGGCAUUUCUUUGCAGGACGCAGUUUCCAGGCUCAAGAACGUGGAGGGAAUUCCUAAGGGUCGCUCUUCACCAAGAGCGCAGAGCCCUGGUAGACCUCAGCAUCGUCACAGAGAAAGCUGUGGGUGCAGAGGCCUUGGGGACAAGGCGGGGACGGAAUUUCGUAUUUCAGAUGACCAAGGCCAAGUGAGUUCGGAGGGAGGCAGGAAGGGUGCCGCGGAGAACCCCGCGACAGGGCCAGAUGGAGGGGGUGGAGUUCGAGUGGGAAGGAGAGGGAACCAGUAACAUGGCUUGGGACUUUUUCAUCCUGAGAUGCUCUAAUGUCCCAGCCGGGGGACCUGUGAGAGCUGGGGCAGGCGCUGGGGGAAGGAAGUCAGGGGUCGGUGCGUUGGGAACCGAUCGCCGAUUCACAGGAGGGGCCUCGUGGGAGCCUGGCCCUCCUCUGCCCCCCUCUAGGGAAGGAGAUCUCGGAGCUGCAGCAGAGCAGCCCCCUUCACAGAGACCCCCAAGGCAGCAGGGCCGGCUCUGUGCUCAUUUGUCAGACAAUAGGGACCCUUAACUCGUACGCAGCACGCGUGGCUGGCUCACUGUGCUCCGUACAGGAUGACGUCUAAACUUGGUGGUUGCCCUUGAAGUAGGUUUUGGAAUGCCCGUUUUACAGACAGACACACCGAGGGUCAGGUUGGUCACGUGGCUUGCCGGAGGCCACCAGCUCUGAUUUCUGCUUCGGAGCUGGCCCCCAGGCGCUAGUGAGAAUGAUCUAACUGAGGGUUUCACAGUAUGGGACCCAGAGGGGUCCGAGAAUGCAGGCCUGUAGAGGGCCAGACCCCGAGAGUCCUCCCCACCACACACAGCGCCUCGUCCUGGUUCUAGGGGCAACACCUGUCUGGUGGUUGCUUUCAGAAAUUUUGAGGUGCUGCAGGCUGGUCCCAGGUCCCUCAAAUCACAUUUCAUGCAGCCCAGUCUCUCGCUCUUAAAAACUAAAUAUUUUUAAGAGCUGGAGAGGGAGAGAGGACUUGCAGUAAGGAAGGAAGUGCAAGUGAAGGCCUUGGCCUUGUGCGGGAACCGCGCAGGGAGCCCUUCCCCGGGCAGGUGACGCCCCACAGGGGGAGGAGGACAAUGGGAGGCUGUAGGGAGAGUAUGCGAGUCCCCAUCCGAUGGGGAAGCCAGUGCUGUGGCUUCAGGACAUCAAGCUGCUUUGGCAGGGGCCGCUGGGUAUGGCUGGGCAUAGGGGCGUAGGGGACCCAAAUCCAGGCGCCUGCCCGCCACAAGCCCAGCUCGUGGGUGGGGGGACGGGGUUUUCUGCGGCGCCCCCCAGUGAGGGCUGCUUAUGCCUCUCUGGUUCCCACAGAGUUGCUCAGCGCCCUGCAGGACCGGUAGGAUGGGCUGCAGGGGGAGAAGCUCUGAUAGGCUAGUGCCCAGGUGCAGGUGUAGGGGAGUGGCCAAGUGUGAGUUCUUCAACGCGGGCGGGAGCGUGAAGGACCGCAUCAGCCUGCGGAUGAUUGAGGAUGCUGAGCGCGACGGGACGCUGAAGCCCGGGGACACGAUUAUCGAGCCGACAUCCGGGAACACCGGGAUCGGGCUGGCCCUGGCUGCGGCAGUGAGGGGCUAUCGCUGCAUCAUCGUGAUGCCAGAGAAGAUGAGCUCCGAGAAGGUGGACGUGCUGCGGGCACUGGGGGCUGAGAUUGUGAGGACGCCCACCAAUGCCAGGUUCGACUCCCCGGAGUCACACGUGGGGGUGGCCUGGCGGCUGAAGAACGAAAUCCCCAAUUCUCACAUCCUAGACCAGUACCGCAACGCCAGCAACCCCCUGGCUCACUACGACACCACCGCUGAUGAGAUCCUGCAGCAGUGUGAUGGGAAGCUGGACAUGCUGGUGGCUUCAGUGGGCACGGGCGGCACCAUCACGGGCAUUGCCAGGAAGCUGAAGGAGAAGUGUCCUGGAUGCAGGAUCAUUGGGGUGGAUCCCGAAGGGUCCAUCCUCGCAGAGCCGGAGGAGCUGAACCAGACGGAGCAGACAACCUACGAGGUGGAAGGGAUCGGCUACGACUUCAUCCCCACGGUGCUGGACAGGACGGUGGUGGACAAGUGGUUCAAGAGCAACGAUGAGGAGGCGUUCACCUUUGCCCGCAUGCUGAUCGCGCAAGAGGGGCUGCUGUGCGGUGGCAGUGCUGGCAGCACGGUGGCGGUGGCCGUGAAGGCCGCGCAGGAGCUGCAGGAGGGCCAGCGCUGCGUGGUCAUUCUGCCCGACUCAGUGCGGAACUACAUGACCAAGUUCCUGAGCGACAGGUGGAUGCUGCAGAAGGGCUUUCUGAAGGAGGAGGACCUCACGGAGAAGAAGCCCUGGUGGUGGCACCUCCGUGUUCAGGAGCUGGGCCUGUCAGCCCCGCUGACCGUGCUCCCGACCAUCACCUGUGGGCACACCAUCGAGAUCCUCCGGGAGAAGGGCUUCGACCAGGCGCCCGUGGUGGAUGAGGCGGGGGUAAUCCUGGGAAUGGUGACGCUUGGGAACAUGCUCUCGUCCCUGCUUGCCGGGAAGGUGCAGCCGUCAGACCAAGUUGGCAAAGUCAUCUACAAGCAGUUCAAACAGAUCCGCCUCACGGACACGCUGGGCAGGCUCUCGCACAUCCUGGAGAUGGACCACUUCGCCCUGGUGGUGCACGAGCAGAUCCAGUCGCAGGACCAGGCCUGGGCAGGCGUGGUGGGGGGGCCUGCAGACCACAGCACCGGGAAGUCCAGUCAGCGGCAGAUGGUGUUCGGGGUGGUCACCGCCAUUGACUUGCUGAACUUCGUGGCCGCCCAGGAGCGGGACCAGAAGUGAAGUCCGGAGCGCUGGGCGGUGCGGAGCGGGCCCGCCACCCUUGCCCACUUCUCCUUCGCUUUCCUGAGCCCUAAACACACGCGUGAUUGGUAACUGCCUGGCCUGGCACCGUUAUCCCUGCACACGGCACAGAGCAUCCGUCUCCCCUCGUUAACACAUGGCUUCCUAAAUGGCCCUGUUUACGGCCUAUGAGAUGAAAUAUGUGAUUUUCUCUAAUGUAACUUCCUCUUAGGAUGUUUCACCAAGGAAAUAUUGAGAGAGAAGUCGGCCAGGUAGGAUGAACACAGGCAAUGACUGCGCAGAGUGGAUUAAAGGCAAAAGAGAGAAGAGUCCAGGAAGGGGCGGGGAGAAGCCUGGGUGGCUCAGCAUCCUCCACGGGCUGCGCCGUCUGCUCGGGGCUGAGCUGGCGGGAGCAGUUUGCGUGUUUGGGUUUUUUAAUUGAGAUGAAAUUCAAAUAACCUAAAAAUCAAUCACUUGAAAGUGAACAAUCAGCGGCAUUUAGUACAUCCAGAAAGUUGUGUAGGCACCACCUCUGUCACGUUCUGGAACAUUCUGUCAUCACCCCGUGAAGCAAUCAUUUCCCCUCCCGUCUUCCUCCUCCCCUGGCAACUGCUGAUCGACUUUGUGUCUCUGUUGUCUAAAAUAGGUUUUCCCUGUUCUGGACAUUUCAUAUAAAUGGAAUCACACAA